GUGUUGUGUGUGGGAUGCUGUUGUUUCAGUCACUGCCAGUCAUUUUCUCAGCUAUCAGGACGUGAACCCGUGUUUGCUCCUUGCAUCCGGGAGGCGCUGCUGAGGGGUGACCUCGAUCCACAGGAAGUGUGCGCUGUGUACGGGAACGUUUAAACCGGGCAUCCCUCGUUUUCUGAGAUGGGACGUGAAGGCCGAGUGGAGAUCGGUAGGCAGCAGCAAUGCCUCUGAAGUUGGGGACAAAGCGGGAAAGAAUCCAUGUGAACAAGCAGUUUGGGCAAUUUAUUUGAUUGUGUGUGUGUUUCCGGCUUUUAAAUAUAAAAAAAAUUUUCAAUUGUGGUAAGAAACACCUAACAAAAUUAACCAUUGUAACCAUUUGUUAGUGUACAGUUCAGCAGUGUUAAUUAUAUUCACGUGGUUGUGCACCCAAUUUCUAGAAUUUUUUCAUCUUGCAAAACUGAAGCUAUUAACAUACACCCAUUAAAUAGCUAUUCAAUUAGAGUUUUUAAAGGCAGGUGGUUCUUCUGAAACACAAGGUUACUGUCAGGCCCGUGGUGAACUCAAAUGUUUGCUAACUAUAGAGAGAAAGAUGGGAAAAAACAAAUGUUUAUACAUACAAUAACUAUAGCUACACAUAGAUAAAAUAUGUCUAUAUUAUCAAUAUAGAAUACAUAGUAAAUGUGUAUUUAUAACAUAUGUAUAAUUUAAUGUAAAUGUACAUUAAAUACAUGAAUUAUAUAAGAAGUUAAAUGUGUGCACGGACGUGUGUGUGCAUAUGCCCAUCCUCGAUUUACCCAAAGACGCGGGCCAUUGCAGAGCUCGCGCAUUCCGCAGUGGGAUUUCUUCUUAUUCCUCUGGUCCAGAUCUCCAGAACUGAUUGUGCUGUUUUCUUUCUCUGAAUGAAUCGAGCCUCAUGAGGGCCCUCUUGGCUCUGGCACCCAUGGGCCCACGCCGCGCCCCCGACCCCAGGUCUCAUCCCCUUUUUCGUGCACGCCCUCCCAGCCCAGUGGAGUCUUGGCGCCCCCGGCUGGAUGGCAGGCUGGCCACACUCCACCACGGGCCAGAUGGAGCCUGCAGUCUGCAUCCGCUUCCCCCCGAGUCACCCCGCAGCCAGGUCCGGAGCAUUCCACUGUCUCCCUAUCCCACUGUCAGUGUCUGCGUGCAGGUGCUGAGCCUGGCUUGGUGUUCUUCUGUCCUUUGUUUCCUGUGACCCUGUGGUGAGUGUGACCCCGUGGUGGGGCAGGGGCUGCUCUCUGGCCUUCCCAGUGGAGAGGAUGAGCAAGGGGCCCCGGCAGCCGAUGGGGGGCUUGGAGAAAGGGCGCUUACCCCACCCUGGGGCUCCUUGGGGCUGCCAGGGGAAUGGUGCCCAGGCUGGCUCUGAAGAUAGGGUAAGAUGACUGGGCCACCAAGGUGGGGGCUGUGGGGAGCGCUAGGGAGGCCCUGCCAGGAGCCGGUGCCCUGAGAGCAGGGCGGGCACUGGGCCAGCUCAGGCCGAGGGGACCUGCCAGACCCCUCCUGGGAGCUUGGACCUCCUUGGGUAAGAAGGAGCAGACCUUGAUGGGGCUGGGCUGGGGCUGUGCUUGAGGGACUGGAGGGUGACAGGCAGAAGAGGGCAGUGGCUCCACAACGGGUAGACGGGGUGAGUCUUGGUGUCUGUCAGUGACUGCCAGCAUGCCCAGCAUCAUCACACGCUCUGCUUUCUCCUGGCACCGGCCUGGUGCGUCUCCCCGGGGCUCGCCCACCUGCGCGGGAGCCAGCACUUGCAGGGACCCACCUUCCUGGGUUGGUCACCUGGCUUCCUUCCUCUCCACCCCCAGCGCCCACUCCCCCUGGCUGGACUCUCCCUCUGUCCUCCGAGGAACAGCUUUUCUUGGCGGCCUCCACCCCCAGCUCCUGCCUUCCUGGAGUGACUUGCCCCUGGGCUCCCUGUCACUUCUGAAUUACUUAGCCUGAGGAGCGUUUCUUCCCUUUGUGUCUCCUUCCCUAGGGCACUUCCUCUUUACCUUCCCGUCCCACCCCUGCGGCUGACACUGAAGAUUCUGCUGUGUGCCAGUGAGUGAGCGGGCCCAGCAUGGGACACUUUUCCUUGGAAAUGAGGGGAAAGAGGGCUGCUUCCUGGGGAACUAGACAGAGCUUGGCAGUCUUCGAGGAGGCCUGGUGUGUCCUCUUUGUUCGAAAGACUGUUUUGCCUCAGGCCAAAUUGUCCGACUCUGCCAAGGCAGGAAGGAGAGUAGGAGAUGCAUGGAUCCCUCAAGUGAACAAGAGAAGAGCCCAGGACAUGCCGGGGUCAUUGGUUGCUGGGGUCAUUGGUUCCUGGGGUUAUUGGUUCCCGGGGUUAUUGGUUCCCGGGUUCAUUGGUUCCCGGGGUCAUUGGUUCCCGGGGUCAUUGGUUCCCGGGGUUCUUGGUUCCCGGGGUUCUUGGUUCCCGGGGCCGUUUCAGGCCACCUCUGGCUCCUGAGAGCGAGGGGAGCCCAUGGAGGCCUGCAGAGGAGAGUGGGAGGUGAGGACAGGGACCUCUGGAUAUGGCCCUCAACAGUACGAUGGUCCUUGUGAUGCUGCCAUCUGGGUGGUGCACGUUCAGUGUGGGUGCCAGCCCUGGCGCAGUGUCAGAACAGCCGUGGUCACGUUGAGCAUGUGACUCAGCUCUUCGUUCCCCGGGGCCAACGCCUUCCCUCUUCCAGGCCAUCAUCGUGUGGACCCCAGCUGCCAACUCCGUCUCCAUCCUGGACUCUGCUUUAGUGCCCUCCCCACCCUGGUCACCGCUGGACUUUAUGUGCCUGGGUGCUCGUCUCCCCCAGGAAGGAAGGAAGUCCCCAAGCUGUCACGGAUGCCCACUGGGCUGCUCUUCGACAGACGCCUCAGGGUCCAAGAGGUGUCUCCCGGGCCAGAUCUAUGUGCACAGGGCAUGUCCCCAGGCUGAGAGGGGCACCCACCUGCCGCUGGCAUUCCCCGGAUGUUGGCUGAGUGGAGGGGCACCGCGUUUGCUGGACAGAGGGGAUGCCUCAGGACGCGACGUCUCCCCUGGAGGACAAUGGCCAUAAUUCUUUUUGAAAACCAGGCAUUUUGAUGUCCAUAGAACUCCUAUUUCAGGGAAAAUUAGAGGUCCUUGAGGUGGGUGUAAAACCAAGCAGGUGGGGCGCUCCCCCUGUGGCAUAUGGAGACAGUCCCAGCAGAAGGUGGCGGCAGCUGAGCUCAGCGCGGUGAUCAGUCUUGGGCCUGGGCUUGUCUGCCUGGCCGUGCCCAGUUGUGUCUGAGAUGUCCGUCUUGCAUCCUGGCAGGUGCUCUAGGGUCCUGGGGGUCUUUUCACCACGUUGGGUCUCUGCACAUAAUACUGGUCCCAGCCAGAUGAGCUGUCAGCCCUGCCCCUUGUGAGAAGCCAGUGGUGAGACUGUGGCCCUGGGGCCUCCUGCCCGCACCUCGGCUGCUCCAGGUUGGUGGUCUGGGCGAAGUGAGGCAGGAUACAUCAUAGGUCCCUUUGGGGAAGGAGAAUCUCGUGCUCCCUCCAUUGUGGUGAUGCACUGAGAGGUGUGGAGAUCUGCAUAGAAGACAGGGCCUCCAGGAGGGUCCAGAGAGGCCCAUUGGUGGCAGAGAGGAUGCAGGCGUCGGGGCAGCCCUCGUGACAGGUGCUGUGUUGCAGCCUGGAGCAGGCCUCUCAUGCUGGCAACACAGAGAGUCACGGAGUCAGAGGCCCUGGACAUUUUGGGGCCUCCAGAGGCACACGUGGCCUGUGAGCCAGCACCUGUGUGGACAGCGCCCUGGCAGUGGCUUCGGUUAGUGGACGGCCUCGUAACCUGUGGUGGCGACGCCUGAGCUGGGGCAGCUGACGCCUGGGGAACUGCUUUUGGUUUCAAGUUCAGAGUCAGAGUGAGCAGAGGUAGCCUUUGGGCUGCCAUAGAGGAGCGCAGCCCACCCCGGCUUUGGGAGGACAGCAUCUGGGCACCGAAGGCAGAGGCCCCGCAGGCUGGGGAUGUCUCUGAAGCACGCUCACGGGUAAGGUGUUGGUUCCAAGUGACCGUGUCUGGCAGGGCAGUGGUGUGAGUAAGGAAGUGGUCUAUGUCCAGGAGGGACGGGCGUGGAAUAGCUCCCCUUCCAAUAAGGACCUGCACUCAGAGCCACUUAUUAUUGAAACUUGCUAUCAUCGUGCAACCCCAGUUUGUGCUGUAGUUGUCAUCAGUGUGUCAGAAACAUUUUGUGCUGUGCUUACUCAGGGAGUCUGGUUCCACCGAGACCCUGCCUCCCAGCCGUAUGCCUGCAUUAUGAGGAUUUGUGUCAUAGCAGUGGCGUGUUCUGUUGAGCACUGUGGCUUUUUAAUCGUUACUCAAGUGUGGCCACUCAGGCUGUAUUCAGGAACACACGGUCUGAACUAACAAAAAACUAGGCGUCCCGGGCAAUCUGUGGCUGGAUGGCGUUCAUCACCUCCCCCUGGGGCGGGUGUUGUGCUCCCGGCAGGUGGUGUGUGUGGUGUGGCCAGGAGGCCAUGUUACUGAUGGUAGUAGACACGUGCCUUCGGGCCAGGGCGGUCGACAGAGUCUGUGUCCCACCUCUGAUGGCGCGGUGGUGACAUCUGGGGCACCAUCAGGAGGGUUGUGAGCACACAGCACCUUCCUCACAUCUGGGCACCAUCAGGAGGGUUGUGAGCACACAGCACCUUCCUCACAUCUGGGCACCAUCAGGAGGGUUGUGAGCACACAGCACCUUCCUUGGUGUUUGGAUGGUGGAGGGUUGUGAGCACACAGCACCUUCCUUGGUGUUUGGAUGGUGGAGGGUUGUGAGCACACAGCACCUGCCUUGGUGUUUGGAUGGUGGAGGGUUGUGAGCACACAGCACCUGCCUUGUUUGGAUGGUGGAGGGUUGUGAGCACACAGCACCUGCCUUGGUGUUUGGAUGGUGGAGGGUUGUGAGCACACAGCACCUGCCUUGGUGUUUGGAUGGUGGAGGGUUGUGAGCACACAGCACCUGCCUUGCUGUUUGGAUGGUGGAACAUCAUUGCCCAGAACCUGCCAGCCCUGCUUUAGGGACCAUCAAAGGACACAUUGAAGCAGAGUCAGACGAGGCUGGCCCCAGGGCGUCCAGCAGGCUGUGGACAGGACAUGACGUGGUCCAGGUGACACUCGCAGUCGGGUGGGGUGACUGCCAGGCACCCCCCUCUUCUCCAGCACCCUCCCCCAUAAGGGCCGGCAAGAGGCCUGGGCUGGGCAAGAUUGCCUGCAGUCGGGGGCACUCACUGGUUGAGGGAGCCCAGACUCCCCAGGCCCCCUGGGGGGCCAUGGAGGAAACGCCCGUCCAGAGCACCUGGCAGUGGGUGCUCCAUGGCAAGCAGCGUCCCCAUGCGAUCUUCCACCCCAGACUGCCCUUCUGCUGCGCCACUGGAGCCUGUGCGUGACUGAGUUGGCAGGACCCUCUCCUGCAGUCAUACUGGAAGGCUGUGAUGGCCUGUAGCGUCCGUGGUGUCCGUGUGCCAGGUAGGCGUGAGUGCCAUCCUGUGGACGCUGUGAGGCGUCACCACUCGCUGAGGUCAGUGGUGUUGCCCUGGUGGGGCUGAAUCUGCAUGGAGGACGCUCAGGCCUGAGGCAGGGGCUUCGCUUCACACAUCCUCACGGUGGGGUUGGGCUGGCCGUGGGCCACCAGGCAUCCUCGCUGGCCCGGUGAGGACAAGUGAGUGGACGGUCCGUGGCCUGGCAGGUGUUCAGGGAACAUUUAGGGACAUGCGUGGAUGGGAGGGUGGGUGGGCGGAGUCCGCAGGCCUGCAGGACAGCAGAGAGACCAAGCAGGCUCUGGCACCUCCCGGGGCACCCUCUGCUCCUCUGAUUCCCAGGCCCCUGGCUCUGCUGACUUCUUCCUACGUGGCUGCCCUGCCCCAGGCACAUCUGGGCGUUCCUGCUGCCUGGUUCCCAAUGUCAGUGUUCUUCACAGCUCUGUGGACCCUGCCUGGCUCUGCGUGUUCUCCCAGCUGACCCAUCAGACCCCUGCGGCUGCCCUUCCUGCCCGCAGCAGGCAACUCCUGAGUCUGUCUAGCUCACACCCACCCGUCCAGGUGCCCUGGCAGCGUCACCCCUCACCUGGGUCUUCAGGCCGUGAGCCUUAGGGACCGUCCCUCUCUUUAGAUCGGGUCUCUGACUUACACAGGGUGCCCGAUUUGCACGCUGCCCUUCACGUACCGCCAGGGUGGGCCUGUGCAGCUGACAGGACCUGUGGCCAGCUUGGCUCUCGUCCAGGUUUAGGUGUCUUAUUUUCAUUUUAUCUGAAAUUUGAGAUCUUCUGAUUAUCUUUGAUAUUCUGAAAUUUAAAAUUUAUCCCAUUUAGCACACAUGAGUUAACUUAAUUUUUAAAGCCUUGUUGGCCGGGCGCGGUGGCUCACGCCUGUAAUCCCAGCACUUUGGGAGGCCGAGGCGGGCGGAUCACGAGGUCAGGAGAUCGAGACCAUCCUGGCUAAAACGGUGAAACCCCGUCUCUACUAAAAAUACAAAAAAUUAGCCGGGCGUAGUGGCGGGCGCCUGUAGUCCCAGCUACUUGGGAGGCUGAGGCAGGAGAAUGGCGUGAACCCGGGAGGCGGAGCUUGCAGUGAGCCGAGAUCCCGCCACUGCACUCCAGCCUGGGCGACAGAGCGAGACUCCGUCUCAAAAAAAAAAAAAAAAAAAAAAAAAAAAAAAAAAAGCCUUGUUUUCUAUUCAUCUGGGGUGGUUUCCUCCUCUCCUGGUCACCCUCGUCAUCAUUGUCGGCAUCAUUGUCAUUUCCCUGCAGCACCUCUGACCUGUGUUUUCCUUUGGUGGGAUUCCUGUGAAUGCCAUUUUGGCUACUGGUUUAUUUCUCUGAUAUUUACUCAAUGUGAUCUCCCAGGUCCUCUGUGCAGUUUUGUUCUGCUGUUCACCGGCUGAAGUUCCAGGCCCUGCUGCCUGAUCGCCUCUGCUUUGCAUCCGUUGGUGCCUGUUCUGCGGACGCCAUAGCAUCACUGUUCUCAGUGUCCCUCCUUAGAGGGGCUUGAAUUACCUCUGUGUCUUCCGGGCUCAGUUUUUCUGUGUACCUUGGUCAUUCUUUUUCUUGCUUCAACUUUUUCAGUGGCUGGUCAAUUGUUCAUAUCUAAGUAUGAGGGGAAGAUACAUUUCAGAUGGAUUCAAGGCUUAACUGUAAAAAGUAAAGCAAGAGAAAUCUCCAAAGACAAUUGGGGCAUCAAGGACCCGUCCUCAUUGACCCCGGAUCUCUAGAAGCGGACAAAGAUGCAAUUGACAGAAUAAAAAUGACAACUUUUGAGUGGAUAAAGAUAUUAGCAACAAAGUCAAUGAAGAAAUGAGAGUUUUGGAAAAAUAUGUGUAACAUUUGACAAAGCUGAGGCAGGCGGAUCACCUGAGGUCGGGAGUUCAAGAUCAGCCUGACCUGCAUGGUGAAACCCCAUCUCUACCAAAAAUACAAAAAUUAGCUGGGCGUGGUGGUGCACGCCUGUAAUCCCAGCUACUUGGGAGGCUGAGGUGAGAGAAUCGCUUGAACCUGGGAGGUGGAGGUUGAGCCGAGAUCACACCACCGCACUCCAGCCUGGGCGACAGAGUGAGACUCUGUCUCAAAACAAACAAACAACAACAACAACAAAAAGUUUACUAUGGAGAGGUCUCUUCCAAACUGGAGAGAAAGACCAACAUUAGAAAAUGAACGCUCAGUGUGACCAGGCAGCCCAGGGAAGAGGGGUCGUUGCAGACAUGCCCAAACUCCCCAGCCCCCAGGGAGAUGCCCAGAAAAGUCAGCAGAGAUCGUGCUUUUUACCUAGCUUGGCAGAAUAUGGCAAGAGAGAUGGUGUCCAUUACAAGGGAGGAUGUAGAGGCCGCAGCAGUGUCGGGCAUGGCUGGAGGAGGUACGCGCGGCUGCAGCCUCUUUAGAGGUCGUUCUGCUCACAUGUCCUGAUGUGAGAAAUAAGCAGAUACUUCACUCAGCCCCCACUCCCAGGGCUGUGCUCCACAGGGCCACAGACCCCAGGACGUGAGGCUCUUUGCACCCGGCAGUCUCUUGCAGUGUUGUGGUAAGAGUCAAACGCUUGGAGGAAAGUCUGUGCCCAUGAGUGGGAGAAUGCUUGGCUAAAUGUUGGCACAGCCACGUGACGGACUCCCCCGAGACAUGGUAUUGAAUGAGAAACGGAAGAUGCUGAGAAGUCUGUAGGAUACAAUUUCAUUUUUGGAGGCAGUGACCACCUGGUGUGUGCAUGUGUACAUAUGUGCACAUGUGUGCAUUGUGAGCAUGUGUGUGCGUGUGUGUGUAUGUGUAUGGAAUGGAGGGAAGUGUGGACAGCAACCACGCAAAGGUUUCCUGUUGGGUGUUUGAUGGUGGAGAGAGCAGGAAAGAGAGAAAGAAGCUAUUGCUCUGAACAUGAAGCAGUGUGUCUGUUCUGUCGCUGUGUAUAAACUGCUUGCUUGUGCGUGUUGCCGCGUACACUCUGUAGAGAGAGGGGACCAGAGCUCCUGGUGUACCGGGAGGCCGGGAUGUAGGAGUGGGAGCUGCAGAGCAGCGUGUGGAGUGCGAGUCUUUGGGCACUCACAGAAGCGAAGCCUGUCUGUGUGUGUGCGCGCGUGUGUGCGCGGGAGCCCAGCCCAAGGAAGGACCCUGGUGGCCUUGCAAGGGAGCCAGGGACAGAGAUCACCUGUGUGUGUCUUUGUGUGGUGGUGUUACUCUUGUGGUAACAACGACUUUUGUAAAUGGGAGUGCAUGGCUGAGGUGUUGCUUCUUAAAGGCAGGAGUAAGGAGGAGGGCCCGGGGAUGGGGAGCGGUCGGAUGAGUAGCUGGGCCCUUCCAGUGCCGGCUUGAGGGCCUUUUCUCUGGAUCACAAACUCCCCACCUGCUGCCUCGGGCAGUGGGUUCUGUUCUGGUUCUGCAGAGGAGAGUCCUGGGGCCCACUGUCCAGGAGUUCCUGAGACAGAGACCCUCAGGGAGGCUCCCCAUCAGGUUCCUAUGGGUUCCUGCUUCACCCUACUGCCCUCGUUGGAGAGACCCCCAGCAGUCUGGGGCCUUGAGGAUGCCUCUGGCCGAGCAGCCACCCACGCGCCCUGCCCUGGUCUGCUUUGCAGCUCUGCGGGUGCAGCUGCUCCCGUCCGCCAGCUGCUGGAUGUUUGUGGGGCAUUGUUGAAAUCUCUGAUGGAUGCUGCCCCCUGCCCCUCCACGGGCUCUUCACUGUUUUGGGUCCAUGCCUGUGCUAUCACUUGAUUCCGAUUUAACAAUACAGGUGAAUGAGGCAGGGCCGGAUGCGCAGGCCCAGAUCCUCAUCUUUGUGCAAAAGCUUUGAGGGACCACAGGUAAAGGCCCGGGCCACGCCGACAGAGGCUCCAGUCUCCAUCCUGCUUGUGCGGCCAUGCCUGAGCCAGGUCCCCUGUGCUGUUGCCACACACGUGUGUGUGUGAGUGAGUCCGUGCGUAUGUGUGUUUGAGGUUAUAUGAGUGUAUUUGUGAGUGUGAAUGUGUGAGCAUGAGUGUUUGUGAAUGUCUGUGGGUGUGUUACACUGUGAGCAUGAGUGCAUGUUUGCAUGAAUGUGAUCGGGUGUGUUUAAGGUUAUGUGUGUGAGCAUGCAUGUUUGUGUGUUUGUGUUAGUGUGUGUGAGUGCCUGGGUGUGAGUGUGCAAGUGUGAUUGAAUGUGUGAGUUUGAGGUUGUGUAAGUGCAUGCUUGUGUUUGUAUUAGUGUAUAAGUGUUAGUAUAUGAGCGCAUGGGUUUGAGUGUGCGUGUUUGAGUGUGUUCAUGAUUGUGAGUUUGUGGUUAUGUGAGAGUGUGUGUGAGUGUAUAAGGAUGUGUGUAUGUGAUUGAGUGUGUGAGUUUGAGGUCAUGUGUGAGUGACACACGUGUUUAUAUGUUGGACUCCUUGUUGGAGCCUGGCCUGAGUGGACGGGGCCGUGGUGCAGGCCAGAACAGGUGUCUGCACAGACAAGGUGGCCUGAGGCGCAGGGUUCCUGCCUGGACAAAGGUGGACUCUGUCCUGGGUGAUUCCCUGUCCCAGCUGGGGCCUGCCCUGUGGCUGCCAGGAGCUGAGGAGUGACUGACUCUGGGGGCGACAGGCUGUGGGAAGCCCUGUGGUGUGGACAGCAGCUGCACAUCAGUGGCUCCAAAGGGCAGAGGGUUAGAGCAAUUGCCCUAGAUGGCAGCUGUCAUCGACUAUCCAACUAGGAGAUGAGGGGCAUGUUGGUCCUUCACCUUUAUGACUCAUUUAGCUGUCUGUAAUUCAUCCCAGGAACGUUCUUAAAGUAAUCAUCAUCAUUUUGAAAAGACCCAGCAUGAUGCGGGGAUGAGCUGUGAAGACAGGUUUUCAAGCCCAAGUCCAGUGGGUGCUCAACCAGCUCCUCUGCUCGGCUCCUCCAGGCGCCGCAGGGCUGCAGGUGCACCAGCCUUUCCACCAGGUGCCUGGCCAGCACAAGAGUCCUGCUCUCCCGGAGGCCGCUGUGCAGGAUCAGCUCUGCACUAUCUGUUGCCGUUAACCAUACAGUGCAUGACCUCCUGAAAAACACCAGACAUGCUUCACAGGCCCCAGGGCUGGCAAGGCAGGGAGCAGGGAGGCCUGGAUUCAGGGGGGCGCUGCAGGGAGUCCAGAGUGCCCGUGCUGACUGGGUUUGGUCUGUCUCUGGGCAAAUCCAGUUUUACAAGUCUGCUAAGUAGCAGUCUUUAAAACUGCAUCUUGAUUGGUGUGGCACCUGUCUCCUGCCUGCGAGAACCAUACCUGCUUUUACUCUACCCUUUAACAGGAGAGCCCCGAGCCAUGUCUUUCAGUGGGAUCGAGGGAGUUGGAACAUUUCAGAGCUGUGGGGUGCCUCCCUCAGCGCAGCAUUUUGGACCUCUAGCACCACUCUCUGACGGUUGUUGGUGGCCCAUGGCUAAGGGUUGCAUGGUUGUCUUUGCAUUUUUAAACUCUGUUUUGACCCCGCAGAGCCCCUUGGGAAAAGUCGGGAUGCUACCCUCACUGACCUGCCAGUCCCGGGGACACAGGGCAGACGGCCUGCCGUCCUGUACAGGGCCCCGUGCAUCUGGGCGUGCUUUUCUCUGCCUCAUGAAGUGUGUCGCCAGCCACGCUGCAAUCAUCUGUUCUUUAAGAGAAAGAAAAGUGGAGAUGACAGGAUGUGGCGGUCCUAUGAUUCUCUCCGCCCACCAGGGAGGAAUGGGAAGUUCCCAUCAGGGCAUGACGCCACUUUCAGUACAAGCCUUCAGGCAUCUGUGCCACUUCCUUUCAUGCACCCUGCACUGUCCUCAGCUCCUUUAAGCUCUUCAUUUCCGUUGUUUUCUAUGAAAGGUGGCUACGAUUCUGUGUGUUCUGCUUGAGAGAAGGUGGCCCAGGCCUGCUGAGACGUCAUGGGCCGUGUCAUCCAGCAACCUGGCUUCCGAGGCGCUGUGUUGAACACUUCUUGACUUCAUGAGUUUAUAAGUACUUCAUGCCCAGCUACACCGUGUACGCGGAAAUGAGAGCAGGGCUUGACCCGUCUCUUGAUUAUCUGCAGCAGUUUUAAUUUAUUUUAAAAUAGAAAUAGCUUUGCUUUUUACAUUAAAAUAAAAAUGCUUUUUGUAAACAAUUGCAACAAUAAAUAAACUUAGAAAGUAGGAGUUUAACGAACCUCUGAGUUUCGCUCACAUGCUUGGGAAACCAACCGGGUUAGCGGGACUGUAGCUUGGAGACAUUGCAGCCCAAGCGGCUGUCUCUGGGGAGCCCUGUGGCUCCCGGGCUGCCCACCCCCCGCCGGGCAGUCGGCUUGCUGCCACCAGCAGGUGUGAGCUCCAACCGUAGACAUGCUCUUGGUCCAGACGUCCAUUUAUUGGGACCCAAAACUCAGAACUGUGGGCAGUUCAGACCUGGAAAGAUGAAAGGGGACCGUCGGGGAAUGGGCCGUGCUGCUGUCUUCCUUCCCGCUUGUUGGCAUCUGUCCAAGCCUUCCCUCCUUUCUUGGAGACUGUCACCAGAGAGGGCCUGUCUGUGUCUUGUCAAACAGAGAGGAUUCCUCCCUGCCGGCGAGCCUGUCCACUGCCUGUGUGUGCAGGUCCUUUGUCACCUUCCUGCAGCUUCCCUGGGGUCACCAGGGGAGUGGUGUGUCACCCGUGGGGUUGGCAUUCACCUCCCCCCAGGUGAGGGCUCUCUGACGGCUGUGAAUAAUCACAGCAGCAGGUACCAGGAUUGUCUGCGGGUUCCCAUCUGCAGGGCAGCCUCAGCUGUCGAUGCCGACAUCGAUAGUUUUGAGUAGAGUUGGGGAGGAACUUGGGCUAUCACCUGGAAUCAAAGCACCUUUAUUUACUGCUUUGGUCCGAAAGAACGCAACACUUAGGAGGGUCCACUCCAGCAGUGAUAAGCACCUCACCUGCAGAACAGGGAGGGCUGCCUGCCCAGGUCUCCCACCUCACCUGGGCAGGAGAGGCACCUGCAGCUUGAGACAGGCAUGGAGAGGACGGUCCUGACCACUGAGGAGUGUCUGUGUCUGGAGGAAACAGCCUGUGCCCCUCUCCUCAGGACGGAGGCCCUUCACUUGUACCCCCCUGUUAUCCCCCAAUGGAGAAGGAAGUGGGUGGGCGGCUGGGACACGUCAGUUUCCAGUUUUUCUUGCUUGGCACCCUGUCAAUCUUGAGUUUGUUUCAAGAAGCUGUUCUGCUGCCUUGAUGAGACCCCCUCCACGUGAAGAAAGGUGAAAUGCAGCAGCGCCAGCCACGCAAGAUGGUACUGUGCUUUGGACGGUGCAUUUCAGGGUCUUCUCAUCGCCCCCUUUGCUAGUCCCUGAAUUCCUCACAGCCAAGUUCCUGUGUCUCUGCGGGCCCCACAUCCCUCACAUCUGACAUUCAGGGCCCUCCUGUGUCUCCGAAGGAAGAGGGUUGGAACACACCUGCAGAGCCACGGUUCUCAAACUCCGGAGCCCUUCACACUCCUGCAAAUUAGCAUGGACUCCAAAGAGCUUUAGCUUCAAUGAUUGAGAUGCACAGGCUGACUGUCGUUCUGACGUGCUUGGGACCAGAAGUGUUCAGGCUCUCAGAGUUUUUGGAUUUUGAAGUAUUUGCGUAUACAUAAUGAGAUAUCUUGGGGAUGGGACCUGAGUCUAAACAUGAAAUUUAUUUAUUUAUUUAUUUAUUUAUUUUGAGACGGAGUCUUACUCUGUCGCCCAGGCUGGAGUGCAGUGGUGUGGUCUCGGCUCACUGCCACCUCCGCCUCCCAGGUUUAAGCGAUUCUACUGCCUCAGCCUCCCUCCCGAGUAGCUGGAAUUACAGACAUACACCACUAUGACUGGCUAGUUUUUGUAUUUUUAGUAGAGAUGGGGUUUCACCAUGUUGGCCAGGCUUACCUCAGGUGAUCCACCGGCCUCAGCCUCCCAAAGUGCUGAGAUUAGUGUGAGCCACCACACCCAGCCUAAACAUGAAAUUUAUUUUUCAUGUUCACCUUAUACAUAUAAUGUGAAGGUAAUUUCAUAUAGUAUUUUUAAUAAUUUUGUUCGCCAAACAGUUUUGACUGUGACCCAUCACAUGAGGUCAGGUAUGGAAUUUUCCACUUGGGUUUUCAUGUUGGUGCUCAGAAAAUUUCAGAUUUUGGAGCAUUUUGGUUUGUGGAUUCUUAGAUUAGGGAUGCUCAACCUGUAUUGGUAUUUAUUGUAUUAGAAACUAACACACAUCUAAAAAACGUGCUUACUCAUUUGAAACUGAAUAAACCCAUUACAUGUUAAAUAGAUAGGUAACAUUUUUAACAAAAAAUAACCGUUCGGUAAAACACAAAGCGUCGUGAGAAGAGAGGCAUCAUUUUACCCUUUGCCAGUCUAUGGAAGGUGUGGCUUAAUGGCGACAGUAUUUCUGCUUCUCACACCGGCUCUCGUUCAGUCCAUGUCCACUGUACCCCUGUGAGAGAAGGGCACAUGACAUUUUUCUAUUAUGAACAAAAAUUUGACUUCACACACCUCUUGUAAAGGUCUCGGGGACCCUCUGGGACCCCAGAUCGCAUUAUGAGGACCGCUGUUUUAGAAACGGGUUUCUGUGUGGCUGGGGGCCUGGGGGCUGAUCACUUAUUUGGCCGAUAGGGUCUUUUGUCAAAGGGUUGUUUUCCAUCCGCAAGUGCCUGUCAGUGACGGAGGCUUUCAGGCAUGUUGUUGGUGAAGCUCAAUUCAGGCCCGUUGUUGGUGAAGCUACGCGUGCUUGGGUGCAUGGUGGUUAUGGUGGAAGAGAUCUUUCCUUACUUAGUCUGGUACUGACAUAAGGUUCUGGGGCUGUUUGUCACCUGCCCUGGGGGUGCCCUGCGUAGGGCAGGGAUAAGUCAGGGAUAAGUCAUGUUUUCCUUCGUGGGGUUGCAGCCAUCUGCCUGGGACCCCACUGGCCUUUUGCUCUCUCGGGGUGUUCAUGGCAGUUGAUGUUAAAUGAUCCAUUGAGCCCAGCGUUUCACACCGUAAGUCAAAUCCUUGGGCCUUCUGUGUGUCUGUCUGAAUCUUUUUCUCUGAAAUUCUUUUAUUUCACAGCAAACGGAAACAAGUCUUGUUUUAUCUGGAUGCCUUCUCCAUUUGGACUCUUCCUCUCCAGAGUUUAUUUUACCAAUAAGUUUGUACAUGCUAGAGAUCAUAGGCCAGAAUGUGGAUCUUUAUCCACUCUUAUGCUUACGCAGACUGGCAAUAAACACACCUAGGCAUCUGCAAAAGGGCCUCAGUGCUGACAUCUCUUUUCCUCCAUGGAGAAAGUUCAGUGCUGACGUCUGUUUUCCUCCAUGGAGAAAGCUGAUGCUCUGUUGCUGCUAACGGACAGUUAUUCUUGUGCGUUCAUCUGUGUGUCUGUGUCCGCCAGUGCCACACGCGUGACCCUGACGACCCUGCUCUGUGCAUGCAUGUUUGUGUGUGUCCGCCAGUGCCACACGCGUGACCCUGACAACCCUGCUGUGUGCAUGCAUGUCUGUAUGUGUCACAUAGUGCCACACGCAUGACCCUGACGACCCUGCUCUGUGCAUGCGUGUUUGUGUCCGCCAGUGCCACACGCGUGACCCUGACGACCCUGCUCUGUGCAUGCGUGUUUGUGUGUGUCCGCCAGUGCCACACGCGUGACCCUGACGACCCUGCUCUGUGCAUGCGUGUUUGUGUGUGUCCACCAGUGCCACAUGCAUGACCCUGACAACCCUGCUGUGUGCAUGCAUGUCUGUGUAUGUCACAUAGUGCCACACGCGUGACCCUGACGACCCUGGUCUGUGCCUGCAUGUCUCUGUGUGUCCCCCAGUGCCACGCGUGUGACCCUGAUGACCCUGAUCUGUGCAUGCGUGUCUGCGUGUGUCCCCCAGUGCCACACGUGUGACCCUGACGACCCUGGUCUGUGCAUGCGUGUCUGUGUGUGUCCCCCAGUGCCACGUGCGUGACCCUGACGACCCUGGUCUGUGCAUGCAUGUCUGUGUGUGUCCCCUGGUGCCACACGCAUGACCCUGACAACCCUGGCUUGUGUGUGCAUGUCUGUCCAUGUCCCUCGGUGCCACAUGCAUGACCCUGAUGACCCUGGCCUGUGCAAGUGUGUGUGUGUGUCCCCUGGUGCCUCAUGCAUGGCUCUGAAGACCUAGCCUUGCUGGCUCCCAUGGCCCUUCCUCUUUAUCCUCUUGGUAUCUGAUCUUCCGAACGUUCCAGAAUCAGAGGGUGGGGGAAUCAGAGCCUCAGAUGGAAUGGUGGCCUCAGCUCAGCAGAGCCUGUUUUGGCCUUGUUCAGCAUAAGCCUGUGGAUUGUGUGAAAUCCUUCCUAUUUUAUUCCCGUUACAGCACAGUGAAAUGGAAUUUUAUUACUUUCAAGUGUAGAGUCCAUUAUGAAACUAAAGUAUAAAUCUGUCCCAACAAAUUAUGGAGGAAAAAUAUCUGAAGUCUUGCGCCAUGUGGCCACGUAUCAUAAAAUGACACUCUUAUAAAACACAAUAGCCAGACCUUACACUCCACAUUUCACUAAGGAAAACAGUGCUUAUUAAACUCACUGUAUAGACAGGAGUCAGAAAUGUCAUAUAGCAACAGUUUGCUUUCUAAAGCUUAAAAUUUAUUUCAAUUUUAAUUACCCUAAAUUCAAAUUAAAUUAAUCAUUUAAUUACACAAAUUAAAAAUGAUUUCAUAUAUAUUUUGUCUGACAAACCUGACUUAGUACCUCUUUGGGAAUUCCCUGUUUUUUCUCCAUUUAAAAUCUGCACCCUGUGUUUGCACCCUCGUGGGUUCUGAAAGAAUUCUUUUCCGUUUCUGCGAGGUUUCUUUUAAGAGGAGUAGUAUGGUGACUAUUUCUCCUACAUGUACUGGUUGUAAGAAAUGGUGGCAAGAAUUAUAAAAUACUUCCUCACUGUCUGGAAAGUCCAGGUAAGAUCGUGCAAGCUGCAUGGACCAGUCAGAUCAGUAUUAUUUGGAUCUUUCUUGGUGCAAGAUGGCUUUGAGUCAUUGGUCUGCACCAGUUUUUUAUUGAAUUAUAAAAUACAUGAGAAAAGUACACAAGCCAGGAGGGAUAUGCGGGUGCUGACUUUCUGCAAGUGAAGGCUCUGCCUUCUCUUCCACAGAUCAAGGAGCAGGUGUUCCCCCCGCCACCGCUCCCUUGUUCUUCCUUCAGUGGCCGUCCCCCACCCCUCCCAGGGGAACCUGUCUGGAUGUCUCCCACCUCGGAUUAGUGUUGCCUGUUUUCACAUUUUAUGCACACGGAGCCCUACAGUAGGCGCUGCUGUGUGUGUCUGCUUUUUCUCAGCAUGAUGUUUCUGUGAUUUAUCUGUGUCACUGCAUAUAGGUGUAGUUUGUUUAUUUUUACUGCUGUAUGGUGUUCUGUGGUAUGAUGACAUCACAAGGUAUUUAUUCGUGCAGCUUUUGGCACGUUUGGGAGGUUUCUGGUUUUUGACUGUUACAGAUAAUGCUGCCGUGUCUUCGUAGAUGUCUUUCUGUUGGGUAGAUGCCUCGGGCUGGCAUUGCUGGGGCAUGGCACUUGUGUGGCUGUAGUACCUGCCACCGAGGGGUUUCCCACAGGGUGUGUGCCGUUGACUGUUUUGUAACCUCGUGUGUGAGUGCCGGCCAACCACAUCCUUACCAACACAUGGUAUCCUUUCGUUUAUAGAUUUUAGCCAUUUUGGUGGGUAUGGAGUGUUCCGUUGUGGCUUUAUCGCGUUUCCCUGCAGUCACACAUGCGCAGGACCUUGUGUGUGUUGAUUGACCACUUGGAAUCCUGUCUUGUAAAGUACCUGUUGAUGUGUUUUGCUUAUUUUUCAUUCAGGUUGUCUGCCUUUUUCUUAGUGAUUUGUAAGAAUUAUUUAUACAUUUUGAAUAUCCGUCCCUUGCUGGGUGUAUGUGUGGCAGGGUCUCUUCUAUUUUGUGGCUUGCCUUUUCCCUCUUCUGCAUCUUUUGAUAAAUGAGUGUUCUUAAUUGAGUGCAGCACAAUUUAUCAUUUUCUUUCCUUCAUGGUCAGUACCUUUUUAACAUCUGUCUAUCUUUGCCCACCUGAAGAUAUUUUUUGUUGUUGUCUUUUAGACCAGGCCUCAUUGCUUACCUUUAACAUUUAGGUCUGUGAUCCAGCUCAUACUAAUUUCCAUCAUGGCGGGCUGUAUGGGCUGUGGUUCAUUUAGCAUCAAAGAGCAGCUGACGCAAGCACUGCAUAUUGAAAAGACCCUGUUUUCCCUAUGGAUUUGGGGUGGAAUCCUCACAAUAAUCAGAUGACUCUGUGUUGGUCUCAUUCUAGCAUAUUCUCCUUGGUUUACUUUAAUUACACAAGUUUAGAAGAAGUCUUGAUAUUUGGUAGUGUGAGUCCCCCAAGCUUGUUUCUCUUCCAGAUUGCUAUUUCAGGUUCUUUGUGCUUCCAUUUAAAAUGUAAAAUUGUCAGUUUUCAAAAAAAUUCUGCUGGGAUUUUGAUUGCGAUUGCAUUGACUGCCGAUUACUUUGCAAAACAUUGACAUCGGAAUCUCAUUGGGGUUUCCGGUCCAUGCACAUGGUAUAUUCCUCCUUGUAUUGAGAUCUCUAAUUUCACUUACGUUUUAUAGUUUUCUAUGUAGAAUUCUUCUACGUCUCUUGAUAGAUUUAGUACUGGAUAUUUGCUAAUAUUGUAUGCUAUUAUAAAUGUUAUCUUGUUUUCAAAGCUUAUUUUGUAUUUGUUUAUUGCCACUGUAUAGAAAUACAAUAGCUUUUGAUUUUGGUACAUUAUUGACCUUUUACUCAGCAAUCCUGUAAAAUUCACUUAGUUAUUUUAAUAGUUAUUGGUAGAUUGUUUUGAGUUUUCUGUGUAUACACUAUAUCAUCUGUGAAUAGUGACAUUUUCCUUUGUAAUCUUUUUGCUUUCUUUUCUUUUCUUGCCUUACUGCCCUGGCUAGGAUCUCUGCCAGGGUGUUGAAUGGAAAUGAUGAGAGUGGGCAUCCUGGCCUCACUCCCUGUUUGGUGAAGGCUCUCUGUUGCCCAGGAGAUGAUGUGUAUUUGGCGUUCUGGACUGGGUUCUGCAGGCUGCUCUCCUUUGUGUGACUCUGGGUUCUCCUUUUGGUUCACUAGCACUGGCCGUUCCGUCACCAGCAUGGCAGGCUGAGGCCAUGGUGGGCACUUUGAGCUAUAGUCACUGCCCGUGAAAUGGGGUGGGGAGGGUGUGUGGUAAGGGACAAAACUGGCCCUCCCCACACUGUCACAUUUCUUUGUGGUAGCUUGGUAAGAUGUUUUAGAAGAAUGUUCUCUGAUGGAUUUAUAGCUUCUAAGACUUUUGCUCUUUGGAAGGUUUAUGGCUUAUUCCAUGAAAUUAAGUCAACCAAAAUUUCAAAAUUUCCAAGCUGCGGGAGGAGGAACCAUAGGUAACCUUAGAUUCCAAGUGUUUGGUGAAGGAAAUACACCCACACGUAAGCGUUAGUGAUGCAUUUGCUUUCAUUGAUUCUGUGUGGAGCAGAAAUGAAAAGAGAGAGAUGUCUUUAUGUAAACAGAUGCCCAGUGUCAGAAACUGCCCACUUGGCAGAGUGACCAUGGCUGUCUUGCUAAAGGUGCUUGUAAAUUAAAAUCACAGGCUCUGUGGCUCAGUGUGGACUUCUAGUGCAUCUGGUAAGUUAGGGGAAAAUACAUCCUAAAAGGCAUUGUGUUUGAAAGUUGUAAUAUGUCCACAUUCGUCUAUUAUUUAUUAGAAUGUAUUUUAGUUAGGGAUGUACAGAUACACAUUUCAAACGUCCUUCAGAAACAAAUGGAUCCUUGAGAUCUUAGUAGCAUGUGCUUUCCAUGUGUUUUCUUAGAAAAGUGAUCAUCGUAGUUCUCUAAUCUGGUUAGUGAAGUAUCAUUAGACACAUACAUCAAGAUAAAAAGAACUAGAUCAUGCUUAAGUCUUAUUAAACCAUUUAAUUUCUAGUAGGUUUUUAUGUUGUGAGUGUUGCGUUGGGUUGUUCAAAGACACACCACCUAAGGAGAAGGUGACGGAAUGGGCAGAAAGAAGAGAGGUGUAUCAGGCAGACAGCUGACUGAUGGGUUUUCAUCCCAUAUCCAAUAGAAAAGACUGCUUUCCUCGUGGGCUUCAGAUAGCGCUGCUUUCUUUAUGAGGGGUUCCAUUUAGUUUUCAGCUGUAGAAUCGUUUGUUCUUAACUCCAUAAUUUUUCUCUUCUCUGCCUGUGAUCUUCAUGAGGGAAUGUGAAGUUUUUCUUUUAACCCAGAUAUUCUGAGGGCCAACAGCAGUUCCCUGCAUUGUAUGUGACUCUGGCUUUCUCAUGGCAGCCCUCUGCAGGCUCUCUGAGGCAUUGGGAGUCCUGAGGCUUAAAGUACCACAAACUUGUGAAUUUCUGGAAUCUUUGAUAUCAGAUCCUUAAAACUUAACUCUAGCCCCCAAAAGGCAGAAAACGGUUUCUUUUGCAAUUUGCUUUCAACUUCAGCCCCCUGUGAGGUAGUUUCUGAGGGGAAUCCAGGAAGACCUUAAAAACGUUCAUUCAGUUCACAGUUUUGUUGUGUGCCUACUGUGUGCCUUGGGCCAGGGGUGCAGCAGGAGGUCACAUUCCAGCCAGGGGCAGGCAGAGGGGCCGACAGAUAAUGAGAAAACAAACAACUACUUAAUGUCAACAUAGAAUGAAAUAUCAGAAAAAGGAAAGAACUUGGAAGGGCAAGAAAGUAGGGUGACAGGAAUGAGCGUCUGGGGUGGGGCGAUCAGGAGCAGUUUCUGGGAGGUGGGACGUGGGUGUGGAGGUGGAGAGAGAGGUGCCUUUCCUGUCCUUACCUGCAGCCUCUAAGCCGUCUGGAGAACUUACAUUUCCCAGACAGCGUUGGCCCCAGAGCCUUUUUCCUACAGCACACCAGGGAUGCCGAUGAACUCCAACCCAGUACUUCUAUGGGGAGAAAAGAAUCAGGCUCAGGGGUGAUAAGGAACUGGUCCAGGGUGAGAGAACACACUGGGCUAGUGCUGGGGCCAGGUGGAGCUCGGGUGUCCCCGCUCCCUGUCUAGUACUCUUUCCCAAGGGACCAGGUAGAGCUCGGGCGUCCCCGCUCCCUGUCUAGUACUCUUUCCUAAGGGACCAGGUGGAGCUCGGGUGCCCCCGCUUCCUAUCUAGUACUUUUUUCCAAGCCAGAGUCCGGGGGUGUGAAGAGAUACAUGUUCCCGUUUGCUCUCAGUGGAACUUGCAGCCAGGCACGGGGCAGGUGCUCAUCAGAUAAGCGAGCACAUGAGUCACAACAGACCCAGCCAGAGCCAGAACAGCUUGGGGUCCUGCUGCAGGAAGGCAGGGUGCCUGGGCAGACCCUGAAGGUCCUGUCUGUGGCUGUUGGAGCUACUUUUUUAGCCCAACUGAGCAUCAUGGCUGCUGACUCAGUCUCCCCAGCUGUGACACGGGGGCUGGGGUCUCCGGGUCCCCUUGCGGCUGUCUGUGGCGUCUGUCUGCCUUGUCCUAUUUCCCCCUCUGGUAAUGAUUCUUCAGUUUUCCUUCGAGGAAUGACCCUCAUUCCCAUUGGUCCCACAUUGGCGGCGCUGCCUGUCAGGGUGUCCUGGCUUCCCUGGUCAAGGGCUGUGGCUCAGCGCAGGCCAUCAGGUGUGGUUGGACAGUGUUCUGGAGGGACUCUCCGUUAAUUCCUGCCUCUGGGUCCCUCCACCUGCUUUGCCAGCUACCCCGUUCACUCGCUGGAGCUUCCUCUGUUUGCCUAGAUUAUCCAAAGUCAAUUUUCUAUUGCUUGCAACCAUGAACUCCUAACAGGUGUACCUUGGGUCUAGCAUGCCUGCUCUGUAAAACCUGAAUUCUCACUUCCUUUGGCUCAAGUACUCUGUGUUCUCGCCGGUUUCCAGAAAGAAGGGUUCAUAGACUGUGGGCAUUGAUAUUCUGUCCAGCAGGUUCUGGAGCUGGCUUCUUAGCCUCCUCAUGUCAGAUCCACUCGUCUACAGAUUCCCGAGUCUUCUGCUUCCUCUCUAAAUCGCAGCUCCCACUGGCUUCCUCCCAGGAGGCUGUGGGUGGUUCCUGGUGACCUGGCUCUCAGUGAGCCUUCACCAGAGGCACCAGGGAAUGACCAUUUCUGGCUGAAAAGGUGACCCGAAGGCUGAGUAUGUGACCGAGUGGAGGGGCAUGUUCUCCAUGCACUCCCCAGUAGCUGGAGCCCCCACCCCCCAGCUCUGGGAAGGGGUCCCCACCCAAGCUGCUUCUGUCAUCUCGGCCUAUCCUAGACCCGACCCCAGGUCCUCUGUCCUGCUCAGAAGCCUUCAGUGGCUUCUGCUUCCCUCAGCGCAGAGGACACAAGAUUCUGAGAAGCCCUCUUGUUCAUGACACAGCCGGAUUCUGGCCACAUCAUGUGAAACAUGUUUCCCAUUAGCUUGGCUGUGCGUGUAAAAGUGAGGAGGAACUCACAUGGUAAUAGAGUUACAUGGGUAUAUGCAUUUUCAAAAUAGUGCCGUUAACUUUCGGACGUUUCAGUGUAGGUGGAAGGAGGUACCGACGCAGCGUGAAUGCCAGGGUGUUGGCUGGCGUUGAAGCUAGAUGCCGUGGGCUGUCACACAGUUCUCUUUACUCUGUAUAUGUUUGAAGUUUUCAUAAUAUAAAAGCUUUGUUUUUAAAGAGAAAUUCAUGUUAAAACCUGUGAAAUCUUAAAUUGCAAAUAUCAAUAUGAAAACACUUUUUUUUUACUUAAAAUAUUUGUACUUUUUACAUAUCCAAAAAAUAAACAAAUGACUAAAACCAACCAGUAUGUGGGGAACUCAACAUGAAAUACAUAUGCUAACCAAGGAAUUUAACUCUCUUACAAAUGCACUCACCUGAUAACUUUGGAAACCAGUGUCUUACCUGGAUACGGUAAGGCUGAGAACAAGGAGAAUCGUGUAUAAAUGGUGGUCUUGUGAAUGUGUUUCUCAUGUGUAGAGGUUAGCGAUUCUGAAAUGACUUUGUGUGUGUACCGGAAUUAAACAAAUGAGAAAAGAUACUGUAGAUAAUAGGAACCAGGUUUCCCACUGUUAGAAAGAUAUUUAAUAAAAACAAGGAAAGAGGAAGACUAAAAUACACCUUGUGAUGUUGGGAUCUGAGGUCUCAGUAUAGACUCAUGAUUAUUCAAGUGUAAACUCAUACAGAGAUACUGAGGUGUGAGUGAGUCCCUACGCGCGCUGCCUGCUGAGAGGGCCCUGCGUGCUCUGUCGCCCAGCAGCAGUUAGCACACCUAGCACUAGAUUGGGUCCGAACACAGUUCUCCCAAACAUGGAUCCAGGGUUCCCUGGAGAAGCCAUUGAUUCCGGGACUGUGACAGGGACAUCUUGUAAAAUCAGAAAGUAAGCAAAUGCUCAAAAACAAACAAACAAAAGACUGGAUUGGAGGCUUGCCAGAAAAACCUAGGAGCUGGUUUGCAGGAGCUCCCGACGGCCGGCGCUUUAGCACCAACACCAAUGGUGGCAGUAUGGGACUAAUAACACAGCGGAUAACGUAACUAUCUGUGAGUCCACACGAACGGAAGCAGAUUACUGAGUCACUGGGAAGAUGGAGCAGUGAAAGCUCAUCCUUGCCUUGGAAUUCUAAGUAAUAAGUGCAGCAAAAAGGAGGUGAUUUGGAUGUCACCACUAGGCAAACAUCAUGACAGUGAGUGUCACAGCCCGGCUGCUCUGAUGGAUUCAGGCCCACGAAGACGUGUGUUGAUAUGUGUCUCUCUCCAGUGAGCUUCGGUAGCUUGGGCUUUUCAAGGCACUUGUUUAUUUCAUCUAAGUUGUCAAAUUUAUUGGCAUAAAGUUUUUCAUAAUAUUCCCCAUUGUCCUUUUAAUAUUUGUGCAAUCUGUAGUUAAUUCCCACUCUCUUUUUUUUUUUUUUUUUUUUUUUUUUUUUGGAACAGAGGCUUGCUCUGUCACCCAGGCUGGGGUACAGUGGCGUGAUUUUGGCUCACUGCAGCCUUGACCUCCCGGGUUCAAGUGAUCCUCCCACCUCAGCCUCCCGAGUAGCUGGGACUACAGGCAUGCACCACCAUGCCCAGCUUAUUUUUUUUUAUUAUUUUUUGUCGAGACAGGGUUUCACAAUGUUGCCCAGGCUGCUCUCGAACUCCUGAGCUCAAGCAAUCCCCCCACCUCGGCCUCCCAAAGUGCUACAAUUACAGGUGUGAGCCACCACACCUGGCCCCCUCUCUCAUUCUCGAUAUUGUUAAUCUUUGUCUUUUCUCUUUAUCAGCUCUGCUAGAAGUUUAUCAAUUUUAUAGUCUCAAAGAAUCAGCUUUUAGUUUCAUUGAUUUUUCUCUGUUCUGUUGUCUUCUGUUACUGUUUUUUUUUUCUUAUUUUGAGUUUAAUUUGUUCUUUUUCUAAUUUUUUAAGGUGAAACCUAAGGUCAUUGAAUUGAGGCCUUCUUUUCUAAUACAGGCAUUUGGUACUUAUGUUUCCUCCUAAGCACUGCAGAUUUUUAUGUUGUAUUUUCAUUCGUUUCAAAAUGUUUUCUAACUUCUUUUAAAUUUUUUCUUUGAUUCAUGAUGUGUUUGCAAAUACUUAGGAUUUUCAAAUAUCUUUGUUAUUGACUUCUAAUUUAAUUUCAGUUUUGUCAGUGAACAUACUUUGUAUGACUUGACUUGUCCUUUUGAAUUCGAGACUGGUUUUAUGGCCCAGAAGGUGUUCUAUCUUGGUAAAUGUUCUGUGUGUGUUUUUAAAAAAGAACGUGAAUAACGUGUAUUCAGCCGUUGUUUAUGGAGUGUUCCAUGAAUGUCAUUUUGGUCAAGUUGGGUGGUAGUGGUCAGGUCUUCUCUGUUCUUAUUUUCUGUCUACUUGUUCUAACAGCUACUAAGAGCAGGGUGUGAAAAUUCCCAGUUAUAAUUGUAGAUUUGUCCAUUUCUUCUUAUGCUUUUAUUAUUUUAUAUUAUUAUUUUAUUUUAUACCUUGUGAUGUUGGGAUCUGAGGUCUCGGUAUAGACUCAUGAUUGUUGAAAUGUAAACUCAUAUGGAAAUAUCGUGGUGUGAGUGAAUACCUAUGCACACUGCUUGCAUCAAGUAUGAAGCCCUGCCAACAGGUGCAUAAAUGUUUAGGACUGUGUGCCCACUUGAUGAACCAACCCCUUUAUCAUUAUGAAGUGGUCUUCUGUAUUGCUGGUAGUAUUCUUUCUUUAAAUUUUACUUUGAUAUACAUAUAACCAUUACAGCUUUCUUUUGAUUAGUUAUGUGAUAUACAUUUGUCCAUCUUUUAAUCUAUUUCUAUAUUUUAAAUAUAACAAGAUAGAUUUCUUGUAGGCAGCACAUAGCUGGGUGUAUAGUGCUUGGGGAAGAUUGACUGUACGUUAUAAAACACAGAGCCUCCUCUCUCCAAAAGCUUUUUAGUCCCUCCUCACACGAUUCCUCUUUAUACUCUGGGAAAGUAGGGUCUCGCUUUUUUAUCCAGUCUGACAACCCCUGCCCUUUAAAUGGGGUGUUGAGACAGUUUGAUAUGCUCACUGAUAUAGUUGGGCUUGGCUGUCUCCAGUUCUGCAACUUAGAUGCUUUAAUUCUUCCUUUUACUGUUCCGUCAAACUGUUUUCACCUUUUUAAAAGGUAAAUUUCUAUGUUUACUGGACUUUUCAUUGAUCAGGACUAUUAUAUAUAUAUUUUUAAAACUAUGUGAUGUUUUUCUUAAUGUAAUGUUCUCUGUGUAAUGUUUUUGUAAUGCCUUGGUGAUGAAAUAGCAUAGUUUUGAAUAGUCUACUGCAACUUUUCUUUUUUCUAAGAUAAGCCCUUGUGUUUUUAGUAUACAGUUUUGCAAGAGCGUGAGGUUCUUCCAGAACAUUUCUAUUAUAGUGAAAAUGCCUGUGCUCUAUUGAAUCUGCAGUUGGGAGAAGAAUCCGUUUCUAGCUGUCAGCACUAUGUUAGGUGAAACCUUGCUAGACACUGGACAUUUGGCUAGGAACCGUGCAUGUCAGCUUGCCAGAAUUAUAGCUUUGAGAAGCAUAAUUGACCAGUAUUAAAGUGAACACAGAACAGGGUAGGAGUGAGCACACAUAGCCUCUUGGCAGUCCUCAGGUCUGGACUAGAGCUUAUUCCUAUUUGAAGAUAAAUAAACAGAAACAAACCUCACCUUUGGACCUGUCAAAAAAAGGGUAUCCCAGAAUGUAUGGAAGAGGGAAAUACCCUGAAGUGCAGAAGAAUAUGCCUCUGAAAAUGAAAUUAAAUCAGGAAAAAAUAUUUUCAAAAGGCUUUGGCUAGAAGAAUACCUGGCUCAACAAAGAGAAGCAGAAGGUGAUGUAUGAGGAGGGACUAGGCCGAGUGAGAAGAUGAUGAGAUGAGUUUAAAGGGAAGUGGUUGAGAACAAAGAGUUCAUGGCUUAGUUAAAAUCUGUAUUUGAAGCCAUAAGGAAUAAAAUGGAUAUUGUGGAAAAUAGCAGCAGUGAAGUGAAGAACAUACUUGAGAGGCUGCCUGGGAAUGCAGAAUAAACAACAGAUGUGUCACCGGUGAAAGAGGCCAGAUCUGAUGGGGAGACUUCAGCCAAAUAGCAUAGGAACUCUGAAGAAGCCAGAACAAGUUUAACAAAAAUAAUAAUCAGUGACAUAAUUGAAGAACAUUUUCCUGAGCAGAAAGAAGACCUAUAUUUGUUGAAAGAGUCAUGUUUUGAACAAAAUAAAAGACUCUUACUUAUGUAUCUUCUGACAACGUUUUUGAAUUUUAAGAUUCAAGAAAAAAAUGCCAGUAGAUUCCAGGCAGAAGAAAAUGGUAACAACCACAACAUCAAGACUCGGCCCCCAAAGUUUUACCUGGAAAGAAGCUGUAAUUGAGCUGGACUUAAACUUCCCUACAAUGUUGAGGGGGGAAUGACAUCCAAAAAUUUUGAGGGGGGCAUAUUUGUGAUCUAAGAUUUUUAUACCCAGCUGAGAUGUGUUUUUUUGUGUGAAGGAUACUGUCAUCUGAGAUUUGUGAGGGUUUGAAAAAUAUGCCAUCUACAUUCCCUUCAAGAAAAUGUCUCUUUCUGACCAAGAGAUGAAUAAACAUUCUGACCCUGAAGACAAAUAAGUCAUUGUCAUUCCUAAGGAGAUAACCAGAUACAGAACAACAGUCAUGAAGAUAUUAAUCAGAGUUGUAGAUACAAUGAACAUAAAGUUGGAAAGCAUCUAGAUAGCCAGCCUUGGGGGCGGGGGUGAUUCUUUACAUGAUGAACUGGUUAGAGUUCUUUGGUUAUAAGCAAUUGGCAAAAAAAAAAAAAAAAAAAAAAAAAAAAUUUCUAGACUAAUUAAAUCAAGAAAAGGAAUUGGUCACACUUUUAAAGAAAGAUGAACACAGAAGCCUCUGAAAGCACUUGAGCUGGGAUCAGCCAGGGACUCUCAGUGGUAGGAGUGCUGAGACUUGUCUCUUUUGGGUUCAUCUAGUGACUGAUCUAUUGAAGAGGCAGGCCUUGGAAAGAGAACUUGAUGAGCUCAGCUGGUGCCACAUGCCACUCUUUGGCCCGACACUUCCCUGGGAGCAGCAGGCUCAUCCGAAGCUCCUGAAGUGGGGCGGGGCAGCUGUCUAUCCACACAUGGAAUAGGAAACAGCCCUUCAAAACGAAGCUUACCAGGUUCAUCUGCAGAAGCCAGCGGACGCCUCUGUUCAACUUGUGGGUUACCUGGCUCAUGAGACCUUGCCGGCGAGGCUCGGCGCUUGAACGUCUGUGACCCAGCCCUCACCGUCCCGGUACUUGUAUGUGUUGGUGGGAGUUUGGAGCUCGUUGGAGCUAUCGUUUCCGUGGAAAUUUUGAGCCAUUUCGAAUCACUUAAAGGAGUGGACAUUGCUAGCAAUGAGCUCCCAAAGCCAUCCAGAUGGACUUUCUGGCCGAGACCAGCCAGUGGAGCUGCUGAAUCCUGCCCGCGUGAACCACAUGCCCAGCACGGUGGAUGUGGCCACGGCGCUGCCUCUGCAAGUGGCCCCCUCGGCAGUGCCCAUGGACCUGCGCCUGGACCACCAGUUCUCACUGCCUGUGGCAGAGCCGGCCCUGCGGGAGCAGCAGCUGCAGCAGGAGCUCCUGGCGCUCAAGCAGAAGCAGCAGAUCCAGAGGCAGAUCCUCAUCGCUGAGUUCCAGAGGCAGCACGAGCAGCUCUCCCGGCAGCACGAGGCGCAGCUCCACGAGCACAUCAAGCAACAACAGGAGAUGCUGGCCAUGAAGCACCAGCAGGAGCUGCUGGAACACCAGCGGAAGCUGGAGAGGCACCGCCAGGAGCAGGAGCUGGAGAAGCAGCACCGGGAGCAGAAGCUGCAGCAGCUCAAGAACAAGGAGAAGGGCAAAGAGAGUGCCGUGGCCAGCACAGAAGUGAAGAUGAAGUUACAAGAAUUUGUCCUCAAUAAAAAGAAGGCGCUGGCCCACCGGAAUCUGAACCACUGCAUUUCCAGCGACCCUCGCUACUGGUACGGGAAAACGCAGCACAGUUCCCUUGACCAGAGUUCUCCACCCCAGAGCGGAGUGUCGACCUCCUAUAACCACCCGGUCCUGGGAAUGUACGACGCCAAAGAUGACUUCCCUCUUAGGAAAACAGCUUCUGAACCGAAUCUGAAAUUACGGUCCAGGCUAAAGCAGAAAGUGGCCGAAAGACGGAGCAGCCCCCUGUUACGCAGGAAAGACGGGCCAGUGGUCACUGCUCUAAAAAAGCGUCCGUUGGAUGUCACAGACUCCGCGUGCAGCAGCGCCCCAGGCUCCGGACCCAGCUCACCCAACAACAGCUCCGGGAGCGUCAGCGCGGAGAACGGUAUCGCGCCCGCCGUCCCCAGCAUCCCGGCGGAGACGAGUUUGGCGCACAGACUUGUGGCACGAGAAGGCUCGGCCGCUCCACUUCCCCUCUACACAUCGCCAUCCUUGCCCAACAUCACGCUGGGCCUGCCUGCCACCGGCCCCUCUGCGGGCACGGCGGGCCAGCAGGACGCCGAGAGACUCACCCUUCCCGCCCUCCAGCAGAGGCUCUCCCUUUUCCCCGGCACCCACCUCACUCCCUACCUGAGCACCUCGCCCUUGGAGCGGGACGGAGGGGCAGCGCACAGCCCUCUUCUGCAGCACAUGGUCUUACUGGAGCAGCCGCCGGCACAAGCACCCCUCGUCACAGACUGGUAUCUUUCAGGCCUGGGAGCACUGCCCCUCCACGCACAGUCCUUGGUUGGUGCAGACCGGGUGUCCCCCUCCAUCCACAAGCUGCGGCAGCACCGCCCACUGGGGCGGACCCAGUCGGCCCCGCUGCCCCAGAACGCCCAGGCUCUGCAGCACCUGGUCAUCCAGCAGCAGCAUCAGCAGUUUCUGGAGAAACACAAGCAGCAGUUCCAGCAGCAGCAACUGCAGAUGAACAAGAUCAUCCCCAAGCCAAGCGAGCCAGCCCGGCAGCCGGAGAGCCACCCGGAGGAGACGGAGGAGGAGCUCCGUGAGCACCAGGCUCUGCUGGACGAGCCCUACCUGGACCGGCUGCCGGGGCAGAAGGAGGCGCACGCACAGGCCGGCGUGCAGGUGAAGCAGGAGCCCAUUGAGAGCGAUGAGGAAGAGGCAGAGCCCCCACGGGAGGUGGAGCCGGGCCAGCGCCAGCCCAGUGAGCAGGAGCUGCUCUUCAGACAGCAAGCCCUCCUGCUGGAGCAGCAGCGGAUCCACCAGCUGAGGAACUACCAGGCGUCCAUGGAGGCCGCCGGCAUCCCCGUGUCCUUCGGCGGCCACAGGCCUCUGUCCCGGGCGCAGUCCUCACCCGCGUCUGCCACCUUCCCCGUGUCUGUGCAGGAGCCCCCCACCAAGCCGAGGUUCACGACAGGCCUCGUGUAUGACACGCUGAUGCUGAAGCACCAGUGCACCUGCGGGAGUAGCAGCAGCCACCCCGAGCACGCCGGGAGGAUCCAGAGCAUCUGGUCCCGCCUGCAGGAGACGGGCCUCCGGGGCAAAUGCGAGUGCAUCCGCGGACGCAAGGCCACCCUGGAGGAGCUACAGACGGUGCACUCGGAAGCCCACACCCUCCUGUAUGGCACGAACCCCCUCAACCGGCAGAAACUGGACAGUAAGAAACUUCUAGGCUCGCUCGCCUCCGUGUUCGUCCGGCUCCCUUGCGGUGGUGUUGGGGUGGACAGUGACACCAUAUGGAACGAGGUGCACUCGGCGGGGGCAGCCCGCCUGGCUGUGGGCUGCGUGGUAGAGCUGGUCUUCAAGGUGGCCACAGGGGAGCUGAAGAAUGGCUUUGCUGUGGUCCGCCCCCCUGGACACCAUGCGGAGGAGAGCACGCCCAUGGGCUUUUGCUACUUCAACUCCGUGGCCGUGGCAGCCAAGCUUCUGCAGCAGAGGUUGAGCGUGAGCAAGAUCCUCAUCGUGGACUGGGACGUGCACCAUGGAAACGGGACCCAGCAGGCUUUCUACAGCGACCCCAGCGUCCUGUACAUGUCCCUCCACCGCUACGACGAUGGGAACUUCUUCCCAGGCAGCGGGGCUCCUGAUGAGGUGGGCACAGGGCCCGGCGUGGGUUUCAACGUCAACAUGGCUUUCACCGGCGGCCUGGACCCCCCCAUGGGAGACGCUGAGUACUUGGCGGCCUUCAGAACGGUGGUCAUGCCGAUCGCCAGCGAGUUUGCCCCGGAUGUGGUGCUGGUGUCAUCAGGCUUCGAUGCCGUGGAGGGCCACCCCACCCCUCUUGGGGGCUACAACCUCUCCGCCAGAUGCUUCGGGUACCUGACGAAGCAGCUGAUGGGCCUGGCUGGCGGCCGGAUUGUCCUGGCCCUCGAGGGAGGCCACGACCUGACCGCCAUUUGCGACGCCUCGGAAGCAUGUGUUUCUGCCUUGCUGGGAAACGAGCUUGAUCCUCUCCCAGAAAAGGUUUUACAGCAAAGACCCAAUGCAAACGCUGUCCGUUCCAUGGAGAAAGUCAUGGAGAUCCACAGCAAGUACUGGCGCUGCCUGCAGCGCACAACCUCCACAGCGGGGCGUUCUCUGAUCGAGGCUCAGACUUGCGAGAACGAAGAAGCCGAGACGGUCACCGCCAUGGCCUCGCUGUCCGUGGGCGUGAAGCCCGCCGAAAAGAGACCAGAUGAGGAGCCCAUGGAAGAGGAGCCGCCCCUGUAGCACUCCCUCGAAGCUGCUGUUCUCUUGUCUGUCUGUCUCUGUCUUGAAGCUCAGCCAAGAAACUUUCCCGUGUCACGCCUGCGUCCCACCGUGGGGCUCUCUUGGAGCACCCAGGGACACCCAGCGUGCAACAGCCACGGGAAGCCUUUCUGCCGCCCAGGCCCACAGGUCUCGAGACGCACAUGCACGCCUGGGCGUGGCAGCCUCACAGGGAACACGGGACAGACGCCGGCGACGCGCAGACACACGGACACGCGGAAGCCAAGCACACUCUGGCGGGUCCCGCAAGGGACGCCGUGGAAGAAAGGAGCCUGUGGCAACAGGCGGCCGAGCUGCCGAAUUCAGUUGACACGAGGCACAGAAAACAAAUAUCAAAGAUCUAAUAAUACAAAACAAACUUGAUUAAAACUGGUGCUUAAAGUUUAUUACCCACAACUCCACAGUCUCUGUGUAAACCACUCGACUCAUCUUGUAGCUUAUUUUUUUUUAAAGAGGACGUUUUCUACGGCUGUGGCCCGCCUCUGUGAACCAUAGCGGUGUGCGGCGGGGGGUCUGCACCCGGGUGGGGGACAGAGGGACCUUUAAAGAAAACAAAACUGGACAGAAACAGGAAUGUGAGCUGGGGGAGCUGGCUUGAGUUUCUCAAAAGCCAUCGGAAGAUGCGAGUUUGUGCCUUUUUUUUUAUUGCUCUGGUGGAUUUUUGUGGCUGGGUUUUCUGAAGUCUGAGGAACAAUGCCUUAAGAAAAAACAAACAGCAGGAAUCGGUGGGACAGUUUCCUGUGGCCAGCCGAGCCUGGCAGUGCUGGCACCGCGAGCUGGCCUGACGCCUCAAGCACGGGCACCAGCCGUCAUCUCCGGGGCCAGGGGCUGCAGCCCGGCGGUCCCUGUUUUGCUUUAUUGCUGUUUAAGAAAAAUGGAGGUAGUUCCAAAAAAGUGGCAAAUCCCGUUGGAGGUUUUGAAGUCCAACAAAUUUUAAACGAAUCCAAAGUGUUCUCACACGUCACAUACGAUUGAGCAUCUCCAUCUGGUCGUGAAGCAUGUGGUAGGCACACUUGCAGUGUUACGAUCGGAAUGCUUUUUAUUAAAAGCAAGUAGCAUGAAGUAUUGCUUAAAUUUUAGGUAUAAAUAAAUAUAUAUAUGUAUAAUAUAUAUUCCAAUGUAUUCCAAGCUAAGAAACUUACUUGAUUCUUAUGAAAUCUUGAUAAAAUAUUUAUAAUGCAUUUAUAGAAAAAGUAUAUAUAUAUAUAUAAAAUGAAUGCAGAUUGCGAAGGUCCCUGCAAAUGGAUGGCUUGUGAAUUUGCUCUCAAGGUGCUUAUGGAAAGGGAUCCUGAUUGAUUGAAAUUCAUGUUUUCUCAAGCUCCAGAUUGGCUAGAUUUCAGAUCGCCAACACAUUCGCCACUGGGCAACUACCCUACAAGUUUGUACUUUCAUUUUAAUUAUUUUCUAACAGAACCGCUCCCGUCUCCAAGCCUUCAUGCACAUAUGUACCUAAUGAGUUUUUAUAGCAAAGAAUAUAAAUUUGCUGUUGAUUUUUGUAUGAAUUUUUUCACAAAAAGAUCCUGAAUAAGCAUUGUUUUAUGAAUUUUACAUUUUUCCUCACCAUUUAGCAAUUUUCUGAAUGGUAAUAAUGUCUAAAUCUUUUUCCUUUCUGAAUUCUUGCUUGUACAUUUUUUUUUACCUUUCAAAGGUUUUUAAUUAUUUUUGUUUUUAUUUUUGUACGAUGAGUUUUCUGCAGCGUACAGAAUUGUUGCUGUCAGAUUCUAUUUUCAGAAAGUGAGAGGAGGGACCGUAGGUCUUUUCGGAGUGACACCAACGAUUGUGUCUUUCCUGGUCUGUCCUAGGAGCUGUAUAAAGAAGCCCAGGGGCUCUUUUUAACUUUCAACACUAGUAGUAUUACGAGGGGUGGUGUGUUUUUCCCCUCCGUGGCAAGGGCAGGGAGGGUUGCUUAGGAUGCCCGGCCACCCUGGGAGGCUUGCCAGAUGCCGGGGGCAGUCAGCAUUAAUGAAACUCAUGUUUAAACUUCUCUGACCACAUCGUCAGGAUAGAAUUCUAACUUGAGUUUUCCAAAGACCUUUUGAGCAUGUCAGCAAUGCAUGGGGCACACGUGGGGCUCUUUACCCACUUGGGUUUUUCCACUGCAGCCACGUGGCCAGCCCUGGAUUUUGGAGCCUGUGGCUGCAAGGAACCCAGGGACCCUUGUUGCCUGGUGAACCUGCAGGGAGGGUAUGAUUGCCUGACCAGGACAGCCAGUCUUUACUCUUUUUCUCUUCAACAGUAACUGACAGUCACGUUUUACUGGUAACUUAUUUUCCAGCACAUGAAGCCACCAGUUUCAUUCCAAAGUGUAUAUUGGGUUCAGACUUGGGGGCAGAAGUUCAGACACACCGUGCUCAGGAGGGACCCAGAGCCGAGUUUCGGAGUUUGGUAAAGUUUACAGGGUAGCUUCUGAAAUUAACUCAAACUUUUGACCAAAUGAGUGCAGAUUCUUGGAUUCACUUGGUCACUGGGCUGCUGAUGGUCAGCUCUGAGACAGUGGUUUGAGAGCAGGCAGAACGGUCUUGGGACUUGUUUGACUUUCCCCUCCCUGGUGGCCACUCUUUGCUCUGAAGCCCAGAUUGGCAAGAGGAGCUGGUCCAUUCCCCAUUCAUGGCACAGAGCAGUGGCAGGGCCCAGCUAGCAGGCUCUUCUGGCCUCCUUGGCCUCAUUCUCUGCAUAGCCCUCUGGGGAUCCUGCCACCUGCCCUCUUACCCCGCCGUGGCUUAUGGGGAGGAAUGCAUCAUCUCACUUUUUUUUUUUAAGCAGAUGAUGGGAUAACAUGGACUGCUCAGUGGCCAGGUUAUCAGUGGGGGGACUUAAUUCUAAUCUCAUUCAAAUGGAGACGCCCUCUGCAAAGGCCUGGCAGGGGGAGGCACGUUUCAUCUGUCAGCUCACUCCAGCUUCACAAAUGUGCUGAGAGCAUUACUGUGUAGCCUUUUCUUUGAAGACACACUCGGCUCUUCUCCACAGCAAGCGUCCAGGGCAGAUGGCAGAGGAUCUGCCUCGGCGUCUGCAGGCGGGACCACGUCAGGGAGGGUUCCUUCAUGUGUUCUCCCUGUGGGUCCUUGGACCUUUAGCCUUUUUCUUCCUUUGCAAAGGCCUUGGGGGCACUGGCUGGGAGUCAGCAAGCGAGCACUUUAUAUCCCUUUGAGGGAAACCCUGAUGACGCCACUGGGCCUCUUGGCGUCUGCCCUGCCCUCGCGGCUUCCCGCCGUGCCGCAGCGUGCCCACGUGCCCACGCCCCACCAGCAGGCGGCUGUCCCGGAGGCCGUGGCCCGCUGGGACUGGCCGCCCCUCCCCAGCGUCCCAGGGCUCUGGUUCUGGAGGGCCACUUUGUCAAGGUGUUUCAGUUUUUCUUUACUUCUUUUGAAAAUCUGUUUGCAAGGGGAAGGACCAUUUCGUAAUGGUCUGACACAAAAGCAAGUUUGAUUUUUGCAGCACUAGCAAUGGACUUUGUUGUUUUUCUUUUUGAUCAGAACAUUCCUUCUUUACUGGUCACAGCCACGUGCUCAUUCCAUUCUUCUUUUUGUAGACUUUGGGCCCACGUGUUUUAUGGGCAUUGAUACAUAUAUAAAUAUAUAGAUAUAAAUAUAUAUGAAUAUAUUUUUUUAAGUUUCCUACACCUGGAGGUUGCAUGGACUGUACGACCGGCAUGACUUUAUAUUGUAUACAGAUUUUGCACGCCAAACUCGGCAGCUUUGGGGAAGAAGAAAAAUGCCUUUCUGUUCCCCUCUCAUGACAUUUGCAGAUACAAAAGAUGGAAAUUUUUCUGUAAAACAAAACCUUGAAGGAGAGGAGGGCGGGGAAGUUUGCGUCUUAUUGAACUUAUUCUUAAGAAAUUGUACUUUUUAUUGUAAGAAAAAUAAAAAGGACUACUUAAACAUUUGUCAUAUUAAGAAAAAAAGUUUAUCUAGCACUUGUGACAUACCAAUAAUAGAGUUUAUUGUAUUUAUGUGGAAACAGUGUUUUAGGGAAACUACUCAGAAUUCACAGUGAACUGCCUGUCUCUCUCGAGUUGAUUUGGAGGAAUUUUGUUUUGUUUUGUUUUGUUUGUUUCCUUUUAUCUCCUUCCACGGGCCAGGCGAGCGCCGCCCGCCCUCACUGGCCUUGUGACGGUUUAUUCUGAUUGAGAACUGGGCGGACUCGAAAGAGUCCCCUUUUCCGCACAGCUGUGUUGACUUUUUAAUUACUUUUAGGUGAUGUAUGGCUAAGAUUUCACUUUAAGCAGUCGUGAACUGUGCGAGCACUGUGGUUUACAAUUAUACUUUGCAUCGAAAGGAAACCAUUUCUUCAUUGUAACGAAGCUGAGCGUGUUCUUAGCUCGGCCUCACUUUGUCUCUGGCAUUGAUUAAAAGUCUGCUAUUGAAAGAAAAAGAAAGCGAACAGUUUUUGUUUGUUUUUUUUGCCGUGUGUGCUCCAUAGUGGAGGCGCUAUUUUCCAAUUGAUGAGAAUGACAAACAUAUAUAAUCUAUCUAUCUAUCUAUCUAUCUAUCUAUCUAUACAGGGGGCUUGAACCUUACUCACCCAAGAGCUUCUUACGGAAUGUGGUAGAAAACCAAGUUGUAACGACACUGUAACCUACCUGAUGCCUGUUCGCGCCCGCCGUGAGCUGCGCACUGGCCGUGGCCACCAUUCACCUCUGUAAUUUAAUCCGUUUCUCUUGGAUUGUCUGGACGUGCCCGAUGGUUCUUUCUUUUGCUCAGUGGAGUUGGAGGUUUUGUGUUUGGUUUUCUCAUUCUUGUCUUGUUUUGUGUGGGUGGAUUUUCACCGACCAAUGAUAUCCUCUUCUGACGGUCACCUUCUUUCCACUUCACUGGAGUCCAGUAUUCUGUACCACAUCACGCAACGUGUUAUCUUGUGGUGUAAAUAAAGACUGCGUUACUUGCCCUCCCA